AUGAAAGGCAGAUCAUACUUAGGAAAUGCCAAGGAGCACCUAAAAUCCCCUUAUGUAACCCCAGAGAUAUUUAAGUUCUUGUCUCUGCAGGAAGCAGGCAAGAGCCCCACCCUCCUGGGCGCAGCCGCAGCUGCCCAAACUGCAGCUGCAGACCCAGGCAUCUCUGCACUCUCUGGGGCCAGGAAGGGCCCCCCUGCCCCUGCAGACUCAGAGGUGUCUGUUCCCACUUCCUGGACUCUCUCUGCUCCUGGCACCCACUCCGAUCUUGGAGCAAGGUUGGGGUCAAGCCUGGGUGCUGUCACAGCCCAGCCAGGUUGUGACACAGCAGCCCCCUGCUGCCUUGGCCCCCUCUGGACUUUGGGCACUGAUCAGUACGAGAGGGAGGCUGAGGUGGGGGCUGAGGGCAGCUCAUUGCUGGUCUGCAGGCGCCCUUCCGCACAAACAGCCUGGCAUGCCAUGAGCUGCAGCAAGAGGCAGAGAGGCUCCUGGGCGGAAGAGGGCAGGUCUCCAGUGAAGCUCCACCUUCAAGCUGGGGAGAGCCUGAAGCCUGAUGGCCAGGCUGUUGGUCCCAUGGACCAGAGUGGAAACUUGUGGUGCUUUUCCUGGGCCUGCCCAUGGCUGCCCAUGGACCAAUCAGCAUGCACGUCCUCUGCUCUGAAGCCCAUAAAAACCCCAGACUCAGGCAGACUUGGGGAGAUGACAGGACUACCAGUGGUGGAGAGGAGCUACCGACCCCAGGGACUCCUGUUGGCUGAGAGCUGAAGAUACAAUGGGACGACUAGCUGCAGAGAGGAGCUACCCACUCCAGGUUCUCCUCUCUGCUGUGAGCUGAAUGCUCAUCAGGACAUCUUGCCUGUGGAGAGGAGCUACCCAAUGCCGGUCUCCUCUGAGCUAUACUGUCACUCAAUAAAGCUCCUUUUUGCCUUGCUCACCCUCCA